AGAUCUGCUUGGACUUCAGCAAAAGCUAAAAGUAUCCUUCAACAGGCUCCUGAAAAAUGAGAUGUCAUCCAUUGGAACUGAAGUAUAUGUAUACAUCUACUCUCAACUCCACUCUCAUUCCUCCAAUGGUCCAUGGUAGAGGCACAGUCAGAAAACACCCUAGUCUCUCUAUUUGCAUGGGGCUACUCAAGCCAAUGGAAAAUGCCAGCAGAUGUUUUGAAAUAUGCAGACUUGAUGACAUUUGGAUCUCUAGAAGUAGGGAGGAGAGCAGAGAAGUUUCUGAAGAAACCAGAAGAGAGAAAAAAAAAAACAGUAGAAUUGUGAGAAUCCAAGGAGAAACAGUAAAGCCAAAACUGGGAGAAAAGGAGAGCAUUCAAACACCUCCAACUGCCAUUCAUGACCCUUUUUGAUCGUACUCUUGCCAGUCUCUCCAGCUCUGUCUCCUAUCAGGCCCUACCUCAGGGUCACAACAGCAGCAUCAAUCAGUUCACAAUGCCGUGAAACUAUUUUUAUGGGGAUGGUGUAGAAAAUCUUCACAAGAAGUCUGAUCUUCCCAGUUCCUGCCACAAUACCAUUUUUUUUCUUCUCAAGAGAAUGUAAACAUUAAAUUAUAGUCCUUCUUCCAAUUAACAUCACUGGGCCUUCCUUAUUUAACACAGAAAAAGGUACAAAAAUUAUUUUUAAAAAUUACUGCCUUUGUCUCGAGGUAGAAUAAUAAUCCAUGUAAAUCCUCUCCUUAAAUCUGUUGUCGUGUGCUCAUCUCUUCAAUAUAUUUACCAAAUUAAAAGGAGACAGAGAAAGAAAGAAAAAAAAUUAAAGAUGAAAGAAAGGAAAAUAAAUGAAGGAAGAAAGAGAUGGAAGGAGGAGAAAGAAAGUAAACAUCUCAGACGGAUGAAUCUAACAGGGGUUUUCUGUGGCAUUAAGCCACUGGCUUGAUUCGAUUCAUUAUGACUAUGUAAACAGUGACAUUUAAACACUUUAAUCAGAGGCCAGAGGAUCCCUUCCACUUUCUGGACUAGAGAACCAUCACCUGGAAUUUUCCUAGAAAAAUGAUCUGUCAUUUGAUACCAAAAAAUAAAAAAAUCUGUUUUCUGCUCCCAAAUGUGAGUGAAGAAUACCAGUUCUGCUAAUUAGGACUGUGUGGAAAGUCGAAAUGACUCCCUUCUAGGCAGAGCACAUAAAGCAAACUAGGAGUAUCUAAAUAUUAUUUUUUUUUGUACUUUCCAUGUCAUUAUGAUGAAAAGAUCAGAACAUGGCAACAGUAUGAGAGGGGAUGCAGUCUAAAGUUGGUCAGAUACCCUGACCAUCCCAUCUAAAAUGCCAUCCCUGGUCUUCUCACAUCUUAUGUAUACUUUCUUUCACUUUCUGGAAUGUAAUACCUGGAAUUACAUAACCAUUUGGUUAUUAUCCAAAAUAAUUUUGUAUGAUGGAAGAGAGCUUGUUUAGACAUAUAUUAGAGAUGUGAUAUCAUAUAUUCUUCUAAUAUUACUGUCUUUAUAAUUGAAGAUAAAUUUUAAAAAUAGCAAUAAAGGAAAUAGUAAUAUCUUCAUUACUCAGUUAUUAAUAAGGAUGAACGACUUUUCCAAAACUGACUAUCUUCCUCUAAUAGAAUGUAAGUACCUAUACUAUAUUGGUAACUUCUGAUCCCUGGUGCUUUAAUCAGUGUCUUUCACACGAUAGGUAUUUAAAUAAUAUUUGUUAAGUAAAGGAAUGAAUCCUACAACUCAUUGUAAUGUUUUCUGCCUCCACGCUACUGCAAUAUUAUUUCCUUGCUCUGGAAAGCCUUUCCUUUUCUUCAUUAAUAGCUGGGAUUCUAAUUUGUCAAUCAAAACUCAACUCAGUAGUUGCUCCUUCUAUGACCCCAUCCACUGUUCAUUAUCUUCUUCUCUAUGCCUUCUUUGUGCAUAAGUAUGAUGUAUAAUGGUGCACAUAAAGUU